ACAGACCGGGUAGAGGCAGGCCCACAGCAUGUCCUCCAAGGUUUACUCCACAGGGUCUGCCAUCUUAGCCUCUCAUCCCUCUGUAGGCUCCAGAGCUAAGGACCACCAGCCCUCGGGUCCGGAGUGUCUGCCACUCCCAGAGGCCAAUGCUGAAGCCAUCGACUUCCUCAGCUCCCUCCACAAGGAGGAGCUACAGAUGCUGUUCUUCUCUGAGACGCUGGCCAUGGUCUCAGACACCGGGGAGCCUCAGGGAGAGCUGACCAUUGAGGUGCAGAGAGGGAAAUACCAGGAAAAACUCGGCAUGCUGACAUACUGCCUCUUCGUGCAUGCCUCUAGCCGAGGCUUCUUGGACAAAAUGCUCUGCGGAAAUUCCCUCCUGGGCUAUCUCUCAGAGAAGCUGGAGCUCAUGGAACAGCACAGCCAAGACUUCAUCAAGUUCCUCAUCCUCCCCAUGGAACGGAAGAUGAGUUUGCUGAAGCAGGAUGAUCAGCUGGCUGUGACCAGAAGUAUCAAGGAGGGUGAGGAAGUGAAGACUGGAGUGACUUCUUUCCCCUGGAGCUCAAUCAAGGGCUUCAUCUCAGAGGCUGCCAACCUGGUGCUGCUCAGGGUGAUGGCCUGGCGGCGGAUGGUGCCCAGCAAUGCCCGCUUCCUGACCUUGGACACCGAGGGCAAACUCUGCUAUUUGACCUAUCAAAACCUGGGCUUCCAGACCAUCCAGGUAGACCAUCAGCAGGCUGAAGUCUUCAUCGUGGAGCAGACUGUCCACGCGGAGGAGGGCAUCCCCAUGUCCUGCCAGUACUACCUGCUCUCCGAUGGGCACCUGGCCAAGAGAAUACAGGUGGGCUCCCCAGGGUGCUGCAUCAUCACCAAGAUGCCCAUCUUGAGGGAAGAGGAUGAGAUUGAGCCACGCCCAGUGUUUGAGAAGAAGCCCCUGGUAUGGGAGGAGGAUAUGGAGCUCUAUUCGAAGUUCCUGGACCGGAAGGAGGAGCUCCGGCUCGGCCACGCCAGCUAUCUGCGGCAGCACCCCGAAGCCCACGCGCUCAUCUCCGACUUCCUGCUCUUCCUGCUGCUGCGCCAGCCGGAGGACGUGGUCACCUUCGCCGCCGAGUUCUUCGGCCCCUUCGACCCGUGGCGUCCGUCGUCACCGGCCUUGGGCUCCUCCCACCGGCCCAACCCUUUCCGCUCCCUGGAGCCGGAGGGAGACGCCCGCUCGGGGGCGGCCUAAGCGGGGCCCAGGCCCGGACAGGGCAGGAAACCAGGGGUCGGGCUGGGACGCGGGCGGGACGCGCCGGGGCGGGUGCGCUUUCCGGGCUGCGGUUUUGGGGGAAUAAAUGGGGCCCUCCCGCUUCUCUGCA